ACUUGGAGAGGUGAGCGCGGCAGCCCGCGCAGCCGGUGACUGGGGGACUGGGUUUGGAGUAGGACCUGCGGCGUGCUCGAGACUCCGACUUCGGUCUUGCGGCGCGCUCGCGCCCGCGGGCCAUGCCCCACUGACUCUAAGUGGGCACUGCCCCGGCUCCGGGAGGGCGAGACCGAGCGCCGGCCAUGGGAAGCUUCCAGCUGGAAGACUUUGCGGCGGGCUGGAUCGGAGGUGCAGCCAGUGUCAUCGUUGGCCACCCUCUGGACACAGUCAAGACUCGCCUGCAGGCUGGCGUUGGCUACGGAAACACCCUCAGCUGCAUCCGCGUGGUGUACAGGAGGGAGAGUAUGUUCGGCUUCUUCAAGGGCAUGUCCUUCCCCCUCGCCAGCAUUGCCGUCUACAACUCCGUGGUGUUUGGGGUCUUCAGUAACACGCAGCGGUUCCUCAGCCAGCACCGCUGCGGGGAGCCAGAGGCCAGUCCUCCCCGCACGCUGUCAGACCUGCUCCUGGCCAGCAUGGUGGCCGGCGUGGUCUCUGUCGGGCUGGGAGGGCCCGUGGACCUCAUCAAGAUCCGGUUGCAGAUGCAGACACAACCGUUUCGGGACGCCAACCUCGGUUUGAAGUCCAGGGCAGUGGCUCCUGCGGAGCAGCCAGCAUACCAGGGGCCAGUGCACUGCAUUACAACCAUUGUGAGGAAUGAGGGCCUGGCGGGGCUAUACCGGGGGGCCAGUGCCAUGCUGCUGAGGGAUGUCCCAGGCUAUUGCCUCUACUUCAUCCCCUACGUGUUCCUGAGUGAGUGGAUCACACCUGAGGCCUGCACAGGCCCCAGCCCCUGUGCCGUGUGGCUGGCGGGCGGCAUGGCAGGAGCAAUUUCUUGGGGGACAGCGACUCCUAUGGAUGUCGUGAAAAGUCGACUCCAAGCUGAUGGGGUUUAUUUAAACAAAUAUAAAGGUGUCCUGGACUGUAUCUCCCAGAGUUACCAGAAGGAAGGUCUUAAAGUAAGCCCACAGCAGGCCUGCGGGGUCAGUGUCAGUCCCUGGAAGGUGGUUCACACAUUUAGGGGGAUGUGGGACUAUAGAGAAGGGAAUCAGGAGACCAGGGGGCUGCUGGUGAUUAUGUAUCAGGUGCCACAAGUGGGUGCUUUGUCAAGCACUUCACCUGGGUGGUCUUUUCACAUGGCCAGUGGAGGAGAUAGGUAUGUGACCUGACAGAGGUUCAGAGAGGGCUGGUAACCUGCCGCAGCCACACAGCUGGUCCAUGGUGGCGCCUGGGCCUGGUCCAUUUCUGUCUGUCUCCGCAUUUUGCCUUCUCAUCAAGAUAGGUUGGGCAGCCCUUCCUCACUCAUGGCUCAGUGCCUUCCCCACUCCUCCUCCCAGUGGGAAGUGCCAGAGCUGCCUUGCCUCCUUCCUGUCCUCAGUCAGCUCAUCUCACCAGCUCCAGGCCCUGUGAACUGCCUUCUGCUCUCCCACCUGAGCCCUGACCCCAGACCUCUGGUCGUGGCUGAGGAGGCAGCCUCCAACACGUUUCCCUGGGCUGUGUCUCCUCUGUUCUUCCUACAGCUCAAGAGCUUAACUUAACACACACCCCUUCCCACCACCUGAAAAGGUGCUGCCCCAGGAUAGACCAGACUUCCAUGUCUGGUGUCCAAGGUAAUACACAGAUUCAUCACCCUCCGCAGGAACUAUCCUGCUGGCUCUUGCUUGCACGGGCUCCUUGCUUUCUUGGUGUGGCUCUUAGAGUCAGCAGACAUGGGUUCAAAGUCAGAUGUAGCUACUGUGAGCUGGCAGGAUCCAAGCAAGCAGCUUCAUGUCUCAGGGCCUCAGUUUCUCCCAGAAUGAUCAUCCCUUCCAUGAAGGGCGGGGCAUUUGUGGGUUAAUACAAAAAGCACUCCAUUCAAUAUGUAACCCAUAGGGAAGAGUUAACCAUUUCUCAUUUGCAUUAGUAUUAUCAGUGUUGAUUUUUUUAGCACCGGUAUUACCCUGGAGCUCUGAGUCUUUUCUCACAUGGCUGCCCCACCCCAGGCCCUGCCAGAUGAAUCUGCCCCAUCCUUCCAGGCCCAGUGCAGUCCGCUGCCAUUCCCAGGAUCCAUGUCCUUGGCUUGCUUCUCCUGUACCUCUCUCAAGGGGCUUCUCACACACCACCACGGGCAACAGCUAUUUCUAUACUGCCCCUUCUCUGCCUCUUACAGCAAGUUUUCUGACGUCCUGUUUUACUCUCUCCCCCAACUUGGGAAAGAUCCAGAGUUGGAUGACCCAGUGUUGAGGUAAAUAACUAACAUGCCACAUGAGAGGGACAAGAUCCAAAAGCUAGAUCAAAGGGCCACACUAAAAGACAGAACUACCAGAAGUCACUGUAAAGUCCAGCCCUUAGUAUUCAAUCAUGGAUCAAUCAUCUCUGUAGAGGAUGGGGCAAUCCGAUUUGAUGAAGGCUUCUAGGGAAAAAUGCCUAAGGGCUUUAGUUUUCAAAUGCUUAUUUUUAGAGCACCUAGUAUGUGGUAGGCACAGUUCUAGGAGCUGGGGACAGAGCAGUAAGCAAAAGAGAAAAAGCCCAUUCUCUGAUCAGCUAAUGUUGGCAGUGAGCGAACAGUGAGACCUGUCCUAAGGUUGCAUUAAUAGAAGUACAGUGGGUAGAAUAAGGGAGGUGGAGGCCUCUGCCCUGACCAGAUUGCAGCUGGAAUGUUGCAUCCACCUUUGGUCACUACCCAUUAAGCAAGACCCUAGUGGUGCCCUGGGAAUGAAGAGCAGGAUAUCAUAGCAUGUGAGGAGAAGCUGGACCCUGGUUAGUAUAAGAAGAUGUGAUACGGAGGAAACUUGAGUUCUGUCUUUAUGUUUUAAGGAUGGAGAAACUCAAAGCUUUCCUAUUCUCAUUAUUUUAAAUUCCUUUUUUAAAUUUUUAACAAGAGCUGCUCUGACAGAAGGGUGAAGCCCAGCCCUGGUGCGGCCUCAAUUGUCUUUUGUAUCUUUUUUUUCUUCUUCUUUUUUUUUUUUUUUUUUUUUUUUUUUUUU